GAAGGAGGGGCGUGACUCGUCACGUGAUGAGGAAGUGCCGUUAGUAGCGUUGUUUCCAGUCUGCGGCUCUCCUGGAUGACGUCAGCAAGGAAGGGGAGGAACGCGAGGGGAGACUGAAGUUCACGUUCCGCUCUUAGUGCGCGGUGAGUUCCCCGGCGCUAAGCCGGGAGACAAGAUCCGAUCUACUGAGAGCUGCGAGGUGAGGAAUACUGUAUCUAUCAUUCAACAAGUUUCAGCUUUCUGGCUAAAUGGCUUUUGUGCCAGUGAUACCAGAGUCCUACAGCCAUGUUCUUGCAGAGUUUGAAUCUCUGGAUCCAUUACUCUCAGCCCUGCGGCUGGACUCCAGUCGUCUAAAGUGCACGAGCAUAGCUGUGUCUCGGAAAUGGUUGGCUUUGGGCAGUUCAGGAGGAGGACUCCAUCUCAUUCAGAAAGAAGGCUGGAAGCACAGGCUUUUUCUUUCACACAGGGAAGGUGCAAUUUCUCAAGUCGCCUGUUGUUUACAUGAUGAUGAUUAUGUUGCUGUAGCUACCAGUCAAGGUCUUGUGGUUGUUUGGGAAUUAAAUCAAGAGCGUCGUGGGAAACCGGAACAAAUGUAUGUGUCUUCAGAACACAAAGGCCGAAGAGUCACAGCUCUCUGCUGGGAUACAGCUAUUCUUAGAGUUUUUGUAGGUGAUCAUGCUGGGAAGGUUUCUGCUAUCAAACUCAAUACUUCUAAACAAGCAAAGGCAGCUGCUGCUUUUGUGAUGUUUCCUGUUCAGACAAUCACAACUGUUGACUCCUGUGUUGUACAGUUAGAUUAUUUGGAUGGAAGGCUACUUAUAUCUUCACUUACUCGAUCCUUCUUGUGUGACACUGAGAGAGAAAAGUUUUGGAAAAUUGGAAACAAGGAAAGAGAUGGAGAAUAUGGAGCUUGUUUCUUUCCUGGAAGAUGUUCUGGGGGCCAGCAACCUCUGAUAUAUUGUGCUCGCCCAGGCUCUAGGAUGUGGGAAGUGAACUUUGAUGGAGAAGUUAUAAGUACACAUCAGUUCAAGAAACUCCUCUCGUUGCCACCUCUCCCUGUGAUUACUCUCAGAUCAGAACCUCAGUAUGAUCAUACAGCUGGAUCCUCCCAGUCUUUGUCUUUCCCCAAACUCUUACAUCUUAGUGAGCAUUGUGUGCUGACUUGGACAGAAAGAGGAAUUUAUAUUUUCAUUCCUCAGAAUGUUCAAGUUCUUCUUUGGAGUGAAGUCAAAGAUAUUCAGGAUGUGGCUGUCUGUAGGAAUGAAUUGUUCUGUUUGCACCUAAAUGGGAAAGUCUCACAUCUCUCCCUGAUAUCUGUGGAGCGCUGUGUGGAACGCCUGCUAAGAAGAGGCCUAUGGAACUUGGCUGCUCGUACAUGCUGUCUUUUCCAAAAUUCUGUCAUUGCCAGCAGAGCAAGAAAAACUUUGACUGCAGAUAAAUUGGAGCAUUUGAAAUCUCAGCUGGACCAUGGCACCUACAAUGAUCUAAUUUCUCAACUGGAAGAAUUGAUCUUAAAAUUUGAACCUUUGGAUUCAGCUUGUAGCAGUAGAAGAAGCUCCAUUUCAUCACAUGAAAGUUUCAGCAUCUUGGACUCUGGUAUUUAUCGUAUCAUUAGUAGUAGAAGAGGCAGUCAGUCAGAUGAAGACUCUUGCUCCCUUCACAGCCAAACCCUCUCAGAAGAUGAGAGAUUUAAAGAAUUCACCUCACAGCAGGAAGAGGACCUGCCAGAUCAGUGUUGUGGCUCACACGGAAAUGAAGACAAUGUUUCUCAUGCUCCAGUGAUGUUUGAGACAGAUAAGAAUGAAACUUUUCUCCCGUUCGGCAUUCCAUUACCAUUUCGUUCUCCAUCUCCUCUUGUGUCUCUUCAGGCUGUCAAAGAAAGUGUUUCUAGCUUUGUGCGUAAAACUACUGAGAAGAUUGGCACCCUUCACACGAGCCCUGAUCUGAAAGUGAGACCAGAGCUCAGGGGUGAUGAGCAAUCAUGUGAAGAGGAUGUGAGUUCAGAUACCUGCCCAAAGGAGGAAGACACUGAGGAGGAAAAAGAGGUAACUAGUCCACCUCCAGAAGAAGACAGGUUCCAGGAGCUUAAAGUAGCAACAGCAGAAGCAAUGACCAAGCUACAGGACCCUCUGGUUUUAUUUGAAUCCGAGUCUCUGAGAAUGGUUUUACAGGAGUGGCUUUCACAUUUAGAAAAAACAUUUGCCAUGAAGGACUUUUCAGGUGUUUCAGAUACUGACAACUCAUCCAUGAAAUUGAACCAGGAUGUGCUAUUAGUUAAUGAAUCAAAAAAGGGAAUAUUAGAUGAAGAUAAUGAAAAAGAAAAAAGGGACUCUUUAGGCAAUGAAGAAUCUGUUGAUAAAACAGCAUGUGAAUGUGUAAGGAGUCCAAGGGAGUCUUUGGAUGACCUGUUUCAAAUAUGUUCUCCAUGCGCCAUUGCAAGUGGUCUUCGGAACGACCUGGCUGAAUUGACAACAUUAUGUUUGGAGUUGAAUGUAUUGAAUUCUAAGAUCAAAAGCACCAGUGGACAUGUGGACCACACUUUGCAACAGUACUCUCCUGAAAUUCUGGCUUGCCAGUUCCUGAAGAAGUACUUUUUUCUCCUGAACUUGAAAAGAGCGAAGGAGAGUAUCAAGCUUAGUUACAGUAAUAGCCCUUCUGUUUGGGAUACUUUUAUUGAAGGAUUGAAAGAAAUGGCAAGUUCCAAUCCUGUGUAUAUGGAGAUGGAAAAAGGAGAUCUACCAACAAGGUUAAAGUUACUAGAUGACGAGGUUCCUUUUGAUAGUCCGUUGUUGGUUGUUUAUGCUACCCGGUUGUAUGAAAAGUUUGGGGAGUCUGCUCUUCGAUCCUUAAUCAAGUUCUUUCCAUCCAUUUUGCCAUCGGAUAUCAUACAACUUUGUCAUCAUCAUCCUGCUGAGUUUUUGGCCUAUUUAGACAGUCUGGUGAAAUCAAGGCCUGAAGAUCAGCGGUCAUCUUUUCUUGAGUCCCUUCUGCAACCAGAGUCUUUAAGGUUGGAUUGGCUGCUUUUGGCAGUGUCCCUUGAUGCUCCACCAAGCACCAGCACAAUGGAUGAUGAAGGUUAUCCCAGGCCUCAUUCACACUUGCUUUCCUGGGGUUACAGUCAGCUGAUCCUUCAUCUAAUUAAACUUCCUGCAGAUUUUAUAACCAAAGAGAAAAUGACAGACAUCUGCAGGUCUUGUGGUUUCUGGCCUGGAUAUCUAAUUCUCUGUUUGGAGCUGGAGAGAAGAAGAGAGGCCUUCACCAAUAUUGUGUAUCUGAAUGAUAUGAGCCUGAUGGAAGGGGACAAUGGUUGGAUCCCAGAGACCGUGGAGGAAUGGAAGCUUCUCCUUCAUCUCAUACAGAGCAAGAGCACGAGGCCAGCCCCCCAGGAGUCACUAAAUGGGAGCCUCAGUGAUGGGCCUUCCCCCAUCAAUGUGGAGAAUGUGGCACUUCUGUUAGCUAAGGCCAUGGGCCCAGAUCGGGCUUGGUCACUGCUACAGGAAUGUGGUCUGGCCCUUGAGUUGUCAGAGAAGUUUACCAGAACCUGCGAUAUCCUGAGGAUUGCUGAGAAAAGGCAGAGACACUUGAAUUGCUUCCACUUUCUGGCUAUUGUGAAUAACGCUGCUAUGAAUAUGAGUAUACAAAUAUGUCUUCCAGACACUGCUUUCAGUUCUUUCGGGUAUAUACCUGAAAGUGGAAUUCUGGAAUCAUAUGGGCCUUGAUACAAAGCAUGCUUGAAAAAUGCGAUCGGUUUCUCUGGUCCCAGCAGGCCUAGUGGGAGAAGAUUCAGCAGGAUGUCAUGACAUUUUGAGAAAAACUAAAUCAUGCUCCUGAACCUUCUGAACGCAUUUGUUAUUGAAGGAAAGACACCACCCCCAAAUCCUGCCAUCUUAUUGGGGCUACUUUUGUCAGUGUCUGUACCCUUGGCAUCGGCAUCUGUGACUCUUUAUCCAUGACCUCAGUGUUUCUUAACCAAAGUUGUACUCAGCAUUUCUUAACCAAAGUUGAAUUUUGAAAAGAGUCAGUCCUUGUUUGCUGGAAUUAGAAUGUUAAUGUCCUAGUAUUAUUCCGAACUACAGUAUUAACUGCUUGUUGCUAGUGGAUUAGACAGAUUCUUUUCUUACUGUGGCUUCCAUGUUGGGAGCAGAAGCUUUUCAUCCUGGUCACAUGAAGACAGAUGGUAUUAUUGACUGGAGUUGAAUUAUUUUUAUAUCUUGUCUGGCACAAUAUGGAAAUUACUGAAAUAAGACGGUGUAUAAUGGAAUUAACACCCAAAAUAAGUAGAACACUGAAGAUUUGAAUUUGAUAUUUAAGUAAAAUGGGACUGGGUGCAGUGGCUCAGGCCUGUAAUCCCAACCCUUUGGAAGGUAAAGACGGGAGGAUCACUUGAGGCCAGGAGUUCAAGACCAGCCUGGGCAACAUAGUGAGAAUGCAUCUCUACAAAAAAUAAAAAAAAUUAGCUAGGCAUAGUACCUGAGGCCAGGAGGUCCAGGCCGCAAUGAGAUGUGUUUGUGCCAUUGCACACCAGUCUGGGUGACAGAGAAAGACCCUGUCUCAAAAACAAAUUAAAUAAAAUAUCUUCAUAUAUAAAUUAAGCUAAUUAAAAAUAUUUUUCCCUGUAUUUAUUUAAUAUUUUCUAAUCUGAACCCAUAUACAGCUGACUAAUUCAUUCUUAGAAAUGUGUUAUCUGUAAUCUUUCCUAAACAGAGUAGCCCACAAGAAUCAUGCACUUUUUAAAAUUAUUUCUAAGAAGCCAUAACAAAGCUGUGUACUAAUAAAGACUGCAGCAAGCACUUGUGUUAUUUAAAUUAUGUAAGUAGAUUGUCAUUUGUCAGGCUCCUGUACAUUUACAUAGCAUGUUAUAUUAAUAAUAAAUGUAAAAUAUGACUAAAGUUUUCAUUGGAACACAAUGUAGACAGGAGGUUUAUUAUGAGCAUUUUGCAGAAAGGUGUGGAGUAAGUAAAGUGUUGGAUGCACUGAACAAUUC